CCCGCCGCUGCAAGACCACGCUAGGCCUUUCAGCCAUCCACCCCGACAACCCAGGGAAGGGACCAUCCACCCACAGAGUUGGGAUUUGGCCUGGGCUUGACUUGGCGACCUGUUUUUCUCUCCGGUAACAGCAGUUCCGUUGAUUCACAUUUGGCUAAGCGUUCAGUUACAACCUAAAGCUCACUAUCUGACGGUCUGACUCGCUCUGACCCCCACCAUAUCCUCACUAUCUCUACCGCUGCCCUCCUCCAGUCCCCUCUCCCGCCCCAGUAUCUGCCCUGCUCCUCACUGCGGGGCUCAAAACUUGGUGUUUGAGCAUGAUUGCCUUCGGUGUGGUCCUUGGCAUUUUCAAGUGUCACAAUCACAUCCCGUUUCCUAGAGGACUCCAAAGACUUGUUAUAAUGGGAUCGGGGGAGAGAAUUGGGUGGGGGGGAAUGGAAGAGGGUCUUUGGUAGUCACUUGUUGGAAGAACAGCAUUGACCUCCCAGAGCAUAUGACAAAAAGAAUGUUAAGCUUCUUUCUAUGGUAACCUACCCAAGGUGUGACCUCCAAAAUUCAAUUUUCUUUGUGGGAGGCAAGGGAGUUUAGAUUCUCCAGGGGGAAGCUUAUUUCUUGUUAAAUUGACUUGCGGUGACAUACACACUGUUCUGCUCUGCUCUGGCCAGCCAUUGCAGAUGCCAUGAUAUUAUUAGAGCAAUUCCCUUAAAGCCAUUACAUUUUCUUUCGAGUGAGAGGAACUCGAGCUAGCUGUUUAAAAUUUUGGAUCUGCACCUUAUUUCUCUAGAAGACAUUAAUGGUUACUGUAUAUGCGCUCACGUGUACCAAGUUUGCAAAAGGUAUUUGUGCAAUCGCCCAUGAAAUGGGUUAAUGCACAUUUAUGUUAAACCCAUUUAAAUGUAAAACAUCUAUCUGUUUUCAAUUUUAGUUUCCACCUCGACCAAAGGCACCAGACUGAAAUAAGACUUAAAAGAGGCUUCCUUGUUUAAAUAGAGGUUUAUAGAACUCUAGUCCUGAGAGCACACAGUAAGCUUUCUGAGCUUGUAGGCACACAAAGCUUGUUAAAAAUUGUGAAAUGGUUCCUUGAGUUAGAAAUAAUGGAAAUGCUUCCAGACCAAUUAAGACAGACAAUUGAUGAAGCUACACUCUCAAGCUGUUGACAGUCUUUGUAAGGUGAAUGUUUAUAGUACAUAAUGCAUAAAUCGGGCUGAUUCUAGGCAAAUAAUAUCAAGUAAAAAACCAUACCAUGUGUUGUAUCAUACUGGAUAGUUUAUAUGGCAUAUUGAAAUCUACUAUUAAAGUGUCUGAGGAAAUCAUAUCUUUAUCAUCCCCAUUUCACAGAUGAAACAACUGAGGCUUUCAAAGAUUGACUUUUCCAAGAUCAAUAGCAGAGUUCAGUCAAGUGUUUUUCAAAUUCUUUCCUACCUCACCCGUUCCCUUCCUUCCUUCCUUUUUGGUGUUUACCUACUUCUUUGUUGUUUACCUACUUCUGAUUUCUGCACCUCUUUUUACUGUUUAACCCAUAGCUUGAGGGACCAUUGUGAAUCAUCCCCAAAAGGCUUUGCUGUCUGCUCAAUAUCAUUUAGCUCCCACUAAGGUGAGGGCUGAUAAAGAAUUAAGGUGAAAACUAGGAAUAGUUUUAAAGAGCUACCCUUUUCAAAGAGAUACGUUAUUUUUGCUAAUGAGUUGUUAAAGGUACAUAUAAUCAAACCCCUAAAGGAUGAUGUCCUAAUUGUAAUGUUUCAGAAAGACAAGUAACAGUAGGAGAGAUGUGUGAGAAAUAUGUAAGUCUCCUAUUUUAUAAACACACUCCUUAUAAGCUCUGUAGACGAUUAACAAUAGAAAUAAUAAAUGAAUAUCUCAUUAGUGCUAUUCUUAUUUUAAAAAGAAUUGACAAAAUAGAUGACUUAAAUAAAAUCAGAACUACUCUGGAAACACAAAAAGCACCCACUUAUCAAAAGUCCUGAAAUCCUCAUUGACUAGUGUACAAAUGUAGCAGAAGACAUUGGUUAGAGAGAAAUCAUAUUUUUACUUGCAAAGCUAGCAAUAAGAAGCGUACAGAUAUCUGCCUAUCUGAUUAUUUUUUAAGGGCUCAUCAUCUGCAAAUCUUUUCUUGGAAAAUGAUUGCUUACAAUAUUUACUUGUGUCAUUGCAUACUAUUUAUUAAUGAGAUUAAUCUCAUUUGCAAUAACGUGGUUAAGUGUUGAGCUUACUACUAGUAAGUCUUGGUUAAGUAUGUGGGCUUUGGAUUCAAGUCUUGUCUUCACAUACACUAACUGUGGGACUUCAAAAAAUGAUAGAACUUCUCUGUGCUUUAGUUUUCUUAUGUGUAAAGCAUGAAUAAUGCACCUACCUCAUGCAGUUUUUAAAAUUUAUUCAUGCAGCAAAUAUUCAGCAAUUGCCUAUUAGGUACCAGCUCUGCUCUAGAUGCUAGGGAUACAUGUGCAAACUCCUUGCUAAUGAAGUUUACCGUCUGGUGCCUGAAAUCUAAUGACACAAUGCAUUUAAAAUGCUUGGGAUGGGACCUUACACCUACCAAAUGCCCCGUUAUUGUUAGCUGUUGGUAUCAUACAUUCUUUCAGGAACUGUUCAGAGUGCCUACCAGAUGUAACACAGAUUGCAGCAUGUAAUGAUGAAUGAUAUGUGUUUCAAUUCAAUUAAGUCUUCUAAUGGAAGAGGGGACUCCAAAGAAGGACAUCAAGAGUAUAAUCAGUCUCUAAAAGGGAAUUCAAUGCUGAUAUGUUAGGGAAGAAAUGAAAAGAAAUACUUAAUUUACCCAUAAGAAAGUGGGAAGCAUACGAAUUACCUUAUAGAAACCCAAAAGUGAUAAGAAAAACAAGUCUUGUACCCAAGCUCUGUAAAACACUAAACUCAUAGUGAAAACACAUAGGGAAAGUAAAGAAAAGAAAAAGAAAGCUUACCUGGAUACAUGUAAUGAAAAAGGAAAAUUUGAAGGGUCAGUUUAUUAAAUUGACCUUAUGAAGGGCAACAGAUCCCAGGCAUACUAGAAAUGGGAUAACCAAAAGUGAAUUUGUUAAAAAAAAAUCCUUGCAAUGGAUUUCCAAAACGAUAAUGAAAGUCCCUUAAAUACUGUGAAAUAAGGAUUGUGGAACUACUCAUCUUUCAUCAUACCAAACAUGUACUGGGAGAUAAAAAGAGAUAAAACAGCGUGUAAAUGAAUUCUUUGCUUCUGUUUUUGCUGAGUAAUAUUCCUACACCCAGGCUUUCUCAAGCAAUACACACAUUGGAGGUAAUAGAUCAAGAAGUGGCAAGUGCUGAGGAUAUUCCAGACCUAAUCAGCAGACUAAUUACAGAUAAAUCACCAAGACUAGAUGGCCUUCACCUAAGUAUAUUGAAGAAGCCUGGUGUGUACGUGACAGCAAUCUGGGGUAUUGCUGGGGGAUUGACUGGUGUCCUUGGGGGCUCCAGUCAGGGGAGGGGUUUCCAGAAGGACUGGGGGCCAAGAAACCAGACCCGUGUCCCUGUGGAUGAUUGGGAGAUGGAUAUUCAAAGUAAACACAGAUUACAGCAAGUAACGAUUUUUUUUUUUUUUUUCUGAAGAAGGGGGAUUGACGUAUUAGAGUUAAAAAAGGAAAAUACAGUCAUGCACCUCAUAACAAUGUUUGGGUCAAGAAUGCACUGCUUAUAUGAUGGUGGUCCCAUACGAGUAUAGUGGAGCUGAAAAAUUCCUAUCACCUAGUGACAUCUUAGCUGUGGUGAUGUCGUGGCACAACACAUUACUUACCUGUGGUAAUGCUUGUGUAAACACACUUACUGUGUUACCAGUCUUAGAAGAGUAUAGCACGUACAAUUAUGUACAGUACAUACUACUUGAGAAUGAUAUUAAACACCUAUGUUACUGAUUUAUGUAUUUACUGUUAAUGCAAUUUAUCAUUAUCUUAGAGAGAACUCCUACUUAUUUUUUUUUUUAAAGUGAACUGUAAACAGCCUCAGGCAGGUCCUUCAGGAGGUAUUCCAGAAGAAAGCAUUGUUAUCAUAGGAGAUGUCAGCUCCAUGCGUGUUAUUGCCCCUGAAGACCUUCCAGUGGGACAAGAUGUGGUGGUGGAAGACAGUGAUAUUGAUGAUCGUAAUCCCGUAUAGGCCCAGCCUAAUGUGUGUGCUUAUGUCUUAGUUUUUAACAAAAAAUUUUAAAACAUGUUUUCAUUUAAUAGAAAAAAAGCUUACAGAAUAAGGAUUUGAAGAAAAUAAGUUUGUACCAUGUGUUUGUGUUUUAAGCUAAGUGUUAUUACAAAGGAAUCAAAAAGUUAAAACAUAUAAAAGUUUGUAAAAUAAAAAAAUUACAGUAAACUAAGGUUAAUUUAUCAUUGAAGAAAGAAAAAAUGUUAAAGUAAAUUUAGGGUAGCCUAAAUGUAGUAUUUAUAAAACCUACAGUAGUCUACAGUAACGUCCUCAGCCUUCACUUCUACUUCCCACUCACUCACUUGCCACUCACUCACUCACCCAGAGCAACUUACAGUCCUGCAAGCUCCAUUCAUGGUACGUGCCCUAUAUAGGUGUAUCUUUUUUCUUUUAUACCGUAUUUUUAUGGUACCUUUUCUAUGUUUAGAUACACACAUACUUACUAUUGUGUUACAGUUGCCUGUAGUAUUUAGUGCAGUAACAUACUGCAGAGGUUUGUAGCCUAGGAACAAAAGGCUAUACCAUAUAACUUAGGUGUGUAGUAGGCUAUACAUCUAGGCUUGUGUAAAUAUACUCUGUGAUGUUCACACAGUGACAAAAUCACCUAAGAUGGCUCUCUCAGAACAUAUCUCCAUUGUUCAGUGAUACAUGACUAUAUGUUUGUUGCCAAGUGUUGCAGGAAAUAUAUUUUAAUGUUUCAGAAAGCCUAACCAGGUUUCCGAUUCCAGUUCCCUCCUCAUUCAUGACCUUUUCUUAUGAAUGGGAAAUUGGCUAAGGAAACAAAAAACAAAAAAUGGAGAUCAAUAGGUAUAUCUCUGAGUGGACAAAUAGCCUCUUCCAGGAAGUAGUUUGGGGAUGGUCUAAUUUAACACUUUUGUAAAUGCUUAUGGGUGAUAUGCAGUUCUUACGGUAAGUAAAAACCAAGCUGCUAAAGUUGAACUAUAGAAAUAACUUAAAAGAUCAUCUAAAUAGGAAGAAAAAUAAUAGAAGAUUAAAGUCAAAAUGGAAGAUUGAAGAUAAGUGUACUUGGAAAAAGCAAUCCCAAGAACAUUUAUAGGAGAUAGUUUUAAAUUCUGUUCCCAUCAGCAGAUAGCAUAGCUGGCUAGUAGUCUCUCAGCUCUCUAAAACACAUGUGUCCACCAAGUUAAAGUCAGUGUUAGAAAAAGUGUAGGUUAUAAAACUCUGUAUUAAUGUGAUGCUAUUUUAAAAAUAUAUAUGGCUGAAUAAGUUUAUAUAAAUAAACCCUCUCUAUUUGUUCAUCUGUGUGGAAAGAAAUACAUCAAAAUAUUAACAGUGACUCUCUCUAAGUAAUAUGGGAUUGGAAGUGAUUUUUAUUAUCUUCUUUUACCUGUGUUCUCCAAAUUUUCUAGAUUAAACACAUAUUCUUAUAAGACAAAACAUUAUGAAAAUAAGAUUUAGUAUUAUAACCUCAGGUUUCAUGUAGUGUUAAUAGAAAGAAAGCUCAUUUGAUUAUUAUUUCUAUGUCUUCUGAAAAUCUGUAGUUGAAAAUUUUUUUGCCUUUUUCUCCCCUCUGAAUUCCCCAUGUAAAAAGGGCAGCAUGUUGAAAUAACGUGUGUGUGUGUGUGUGUGUGUGUGUGUGUGUUUGGUGUUAGGAAAAAAUGUGGUUGAUGUGCUUUUUAAAAUAGAACUAGGAAAUGUAAAAAGAUUUCGUUUUUACAUUCAAUGGAUUUUACAUUCAAAUCCAUAACUCAGGAUUUGAAGAACAAAGUUAUAGAAGCAUUGCUGAUUUCUUUCUAGACUGUAAGCGCUAUGAGGACAGGCACCGAAUCUGUUUCUUUCCUUUCUGACUGUGUAGUGCUUGCCUUGGUGUCUAGCACAGAAGACUCUCCCAGUAAAUACGUUGGAAUGUUUUGAAUUGAAUGAUAGGAUUAAAAACUCUGAUAAGCAUGUAGAAAUUUGAAAUAAGAGUUUCUAGGGCCCAUUGUAUCCUCUGAGGUCAUAUGAUUCACUCACGUUUUAGUUUGUUUCUCUGUAAGUUAUCCUGGCAGUCUUUGUAUUAUAUGACCCCUGGGCCACAAAAGUGGUUUGUGCUGGUCAUCUGGGAUCCUCUGGCUUAUUCUCAAGUUUUGAUCCAGCUCCUGCCACUUGCAUCCAUCUCUCAUUUCAGUUGGUUUUGUGCUUUGGGGCUGGUGUUUUGUUUCUUUCCUUGGCUCUGGAUUUUGUCUCUCUUUCAGCCUUUGGCUUGGGUUCAUCAUCUUUUUCUCCCACUGUGGACACCAGUGUAUAUAAUCCCAGUUAGCUCUGGCCCCCUUUAAAAAAAAAACUUAUAUUUUAGGUUCAGGGGUACAUACACAGGUUUGUUAGAUAGGUAAAUUGCAUGUCACAGGGAUUUGGUGUACAGAUUAUUUCCUCACCCAGGAAAUAAGCAUAGUUCUCAAUAGGUAAUUUUUCAUUCCUCACUCUCUUCCCACCCUUUACCCUCAAGUAGACCCCAGUGUUUGUUGUUCUCUUCUUUGUGUCCACGUGUUCUCAAUGUUUAGCUCUCACUUAUAAGAGCAUGUGGUAUUAGGUUUUCUGUUCUUGGAUUAGUUCACUUAGGAUAAUGGCCUCCAGCUUCAUCCAUGUUGCUGCAAAGUACGUGAUCUCAUUUUUAUGGCUGCAUAGUAUUCCGUGGUGUAUAUGUACCACAUUUUUUUUAAUCCAGUUUACUGUUGAUGAGCAUUUAGGUUGAUUCCAUGUAUUUGCAUUUAGGUUGAUUCCAUGUAUUUGCUAUUAUGGAUAGUGUUGCAACGAACAUACACAUUCAUGUGUUUUUAUGUAGAACAAUUUGUAUUCCUUUGGGUAUAUACCCAAUAAUGGGAUUGCUGGGUCAAGUGGUAAUUCUGUUUUAAGUUCUUUGAGAAAUUGCCAAACUGCUUUCCACAGUGGCUGAUCUAAUUUACAAUUCCACCAGCAGUGUAUAAGAGUUCCCUUUUCUCUGCAACCAUGUCAGCAUCUUUUAUUUUUUGGCUGACCCUUCUUGAUAAGCUAGAAUCUUUUAAAGAGUGGUUUAUACCACAAACUAUUAAAUAUUAACAAUUGAAUAUUACUGUGGUCUGAAUAGUGGCAUACCUCCAAAAUUAUGUGUUGGAACAUAAUCCCCAAUGUAAUAGUAUCAAAAGGUGGGGCCUUUUGGACAGAGCCCUCAUGAGUGGGAUUAGUGCCUUUAUAAAAGAGGUUGAAAGGAGCUCCCUUGUUUCUUCUGCCAUGUGAGGACACAGCAACAAGGUGCCAUCCAUGAGGCAGAGAAUGAGCCCUCACCAGACACCAGAUCUGCUGGUAUUGUCAUCUUGGACUUCUCAGCCUUCAGGACUGUGAGCAAUAAAAUUCUGUUAUUUAUAAAUUACCCCGGCUAAGGCAUUUUAUUAUAGCAGCCUGAUGGACUAAGACAAAUAUUAACACCUGAUCCCCAGAAGGGAUCUAGGAGUCAUUGUAGAUUGUUCUCCAAUAUUAGCUUAAUAAGGCACUGUAGUCAGAUUAUUCAGUAAUAUCCCUGGUAUUGUCAGCAGGAGUCUUGGCAGAAGAACAGAAAAUUUUAUGUUGUUUUUACAUAAAAUCUGGUAUAUAUGUUACAACAUGCAACCCUUAUUGUCAUUUUCAAGAAAGACAGAUAGGGAGGAAUUGGAUAAGAGCAAUAACAUGGUCAAGCCAGUGCCCAGGACUUUGAGUGAGGACUUAGGGGAAGUAGCUAUUUUCUGACGACAGAAUGUAAAUAGAACUCUGGCUUGGAAGAUAAAGACUCAAGGGAUAGGAGCCUAGUGUAUACAUUAUGAAGGUCACUGCCUGCUAGAGAGUCUUCUUUAACUAAUCCGACUCCAAGACUAACACAGACCAACCCAAAGACUACGUAUAACCAGAAGGCCAUAGGGCAGGAACUCCUGCUUGCCAUCAGGUGCUUCUCUUUGAGGGAGUUCUUGAAAUGGUCCACGGCUCAGGUGUGAAGAGAUGAGAUCUAUAUUGGACAGGUUCUGGAGCCAUCGUGGCUUAGAAGCCUCAUUCCCCUAGGAGUUGAUAUCUCUUGUAACUCCAUAGACAAAGCUUCCAAGGUCUCAUAGGGAUGUGCCCAGUUUCCAGAAUCAUGGCCCUCAGGGAAGCCCCAAGCAUGGUGUCCUAUCAGGUAAUUUUAGUUUUCAACCAGCCUACCAAUUACAGUCAUAGCUGUAACUUGUUACUAUGACGUUUUUACUCUUAUCAGGUUGCUACAAUAAAACAGCUAGACAGAUACCCAAAGUCAAAUUCUCAUGCACAGUUACAAGUAGAGUGAAUUUGCAUUAUUUUUCACAAAAAUUAAAAACUAGAACUAGAAUACAUCUGUUGAUAUCUGAAAACAAGGGAUUUUAGACAGAAAGCAAUGAGGUCAGACUAUGUAAUACCCCUACCUCCUGUCCUGCAUUCCCCCCUGCUCAUCCUUAUUCUCUGGACAAGAGGAUGCAAAGUAAAAUUAAAAAUAGGUUCAAAAGUGUUUAGGUGUAUGCGUGAGUAAUUACCACAUAAUGGAUUGUUAGGCAAAACGAAAGUAUUGGGUGUAAAAUCUUCAUCUUUUGCUAGAAUUUUUAUUGAAUUCUUUUAAUUCAGAUUCCUGAUCACCUAACCGAAUGAAUUCACAACAACUUUUGCAGCAGUUAUGACUUGUUCUCAGCCAUAGAUAAAGGAAUUCGUAAACCCAGGAUUGUCCUACUAUUUCUGCCUUUUCUUUUGGAAAUCAUUAUUGCUACUUGAACUACCAAAAAAAGUAUAUUUAAGCAUUCCAGGUGAUUAAAUAACAAUGCAGUUAGUGUGUUUUUGUAGUAGGAUUUUGGGUAAACAUUUUCAAAAAAUAUUUAAUAUUUUUAUGACCUAAAAAAGCAGGAGAGAUAAAGGUUAUUUUAAGCACAAUUUUUAGUGCCUUGUAGUAUAACAUAUUAGCCCAGAUGUACAUGUUACUUAAAUUUCUAUCAAGAUAUCUAGAAAUACUAGUUCUUUUAUGCUGUUACAGAACUUUAGAUAAUAUAAUCAUUUACUUGCACUUAUAAUAACAGCAUUUAUUACCCUCUACUUUUACUUACAUGGUUUUUCAUCCACAGGACUCUACCUGCUUGUGAGAGAUUAUGUUAAUUUUCCAUUGGCAGAGAGGCAAUGUAGAGGGAAGGUUGGAGGUCUGGGCUCUCCUGUAGUGUAAUUCUGCCUCCACCAGUUGCUACCUGUGUGACCUUGGGCAAGUUAUUUAGUUUCCUCCAAUUUUACCGGCUACACCAUUAACUAGCUGGCUGACCUUUAGCCAGUAGGUCACCCACUGGGCAUCAUUUGCUUCAGCUGUACAAAUCAAAAGGCUUUACUAAAUUCCCAGAUGUGUAGGAACCAACAUAUAGUUUUUGACAUUUAAAAUUACCCAUUAAUGCUGAUCUAAUAAAAUUGCUUUGAUUAACUGAAAGUGUGGCAUAAUAUUGGUAUAUAGACUAAAAUAAAUAAACAUUCAAGAAUUCUUGUCUUCUAAGAACAUGAGACCUCUAAUAAAUAAUUUAAAAGGUGUAGCACAUCCCCCCAGAAUAUAUUUUCUUGCUAUGUAGAUCUUCACUGUUCUUUGACUCGCCAUGUGGAAUACAUUUAAUUUCUUAGAAAAUUUUCAAUCUUGGAGAAAAAAAUUCACUUUCAAGUGUUCUAAAAAUAUUGCCAUUUAAAAAUACUGACUUUAAUAGAAGUAAUAUCCUGCGUUUAUAUAGUGGCUUUUCAUGGAAGAUCAAAGGAAUGGUAUUAGAAGUACAUGGUUUUUCUUUUAUGUAUAACUUCAUAGGAGAAUUUUCUUUUGUUGAGUUCUUUUAAUUCAGAUUCCCGAUCUGAAUUAAAAGAACUACCCGAGUGAAUUCACAAAAAGUUUGCAGCAGUUGUGCCUUUUUCUCAGUCAGGUGUGUCCUUGGUCAGGGGUGUCCUUCCAUCCAUUAUUCCACAAUUUACAAUGCUUCUCAUCCUUCAAAGCCUAGUUCAAUGCAGCCUCCCCAAAGAUGCCUUUUCUCCUGAUUCCCUCAUCAGUGUAAAUUUUGCUCUUUUACGUAUACCUGUAUUUUGUAGUAACAUAUUCUUUGUUACAUUCUCUACAUUCUCUUGUUACCUGUAUUUUUAGUCUUAUUUCUCAUGGAUGCCAACAUGAACAUAAUGUUUUGCAUAGAGUAAGCCCUCAGUCAAUAUGCUUAAUAGAAUAAUGCCUUUCAUAGAGAAAAGCUGUAAAGAUCUGGGGGGAAUCACAAAGGAUUGCAUCUUAGACUCGUUGUGCUACUAUAACAAAAUACCUGAGACUGGGAAAUUUAUAUCAAACAAAAAUUUAUUUCUCACACAUCUGAGGCUGAGAAGUCCAAGAUCAAGGCACCAGCUGGUGAGGGCACAGUCUCUCUGCUUCUAAGAUGGCACUUUGUUGCUGUGUCCUCACACAGGGAAAGACAGAAGAGCAAGUGAGUUAAGGCCAUGUGAAGAAGUCUCUUCUAUAAGGCCCUAAUCCCAUUUGCGAGGGAGGAGCCUUCAUGCAUAAUCACCUCUUGAAAGUUCCAUCUCUUAAUACUGUCACAUGACCACACCUGAAUUUUGGAGGGAUCACAGGGAAACCAUAGCAGAUUGGUUUAGAUGGAAGGGAUAGGUUUUGCAUUAUAUGACAAACUGUUACCUAAUUUUGGUCCCUGGAUGUCCAGGAAGAACAAAUGAAUACCACAAGCUAUACACAUUCUUCUUAGAGACUCUACUCUGCUGCUGUGUCCUUAUAAUGAAUACCUUUUAGGUAUUGAGGGUAUUCACAAAACAGACUCUAAGCCCUGAGUUGCCCAUGACCUAGGACUUUGGAAAGUUAGGUAUGAUAUUUUUACCCUUACCCUGGGGAAGGCACAAAACUAUUAAUGAAGGAUAUGCCCCCAUGACCCAAAUGCUAGGCCCCACCUUCAACACUUGGGAUCACAUUUCAACAUGAGAUUUGGAUGGGAUACAACACCCAAACCAUAUCAGUGGGUAAUUUCUAUUUUUAAAAUAUACAAAAGUUUAAGGAAGAAAAUAAUCAUUCCCCAUUUUAUCACACAGAUUUAAUUAUUCGUGUGUAAUUUCUUUAUUAUUUUAAUGAUAUUCUUUUUCUCUGUGUCACAUGGUGGCUACCUAGUUAUGGAUACAGCAUAUGUUGAAUGUAUUUGAUCCUUAUCUUCCUAGAGUAAACCAGAGGCCAAUAUAGCAAAUUUACUAUGUAUAAAGAUGUACACUGUUCUUCUAUGCUACUGAAAAACUCUUUCAUCAGUAGUCUCCCAUGUGGCCUCCUAUUUGUGGGAGGGAAUAAUGUGCAUAGUUAGGGCUGGUAUUUUUUAAACAAAGAAAUAGACAAGGCCAGAUCUGUUUAAUCUCUAACGGCCAGUGUUCUUUCUGUUCAUUCCCAUAGAUUAGAAUCACAGCCAACUGGCUUAAAAUGUUGUUUUAAGGAGCACCAGGUGAGAGGUGGCCAGAUCAGCAUCAGCUCCCCACAGUCCUGAUAAAUGACUCAGGUUUGAACUCCUCCUGUUGCCAAUGUUGUUAUUCUUUGGUAAGGUGAACCAGGCAAGCAAAAAUCAACAUGGUACAAAAAAAUUUUUCUCACCAAAGCUAUUUGGAGGCUCAACUUUCUCAAUGAAGGGCACUGCAUUUCAUAGAUAGAAUAGCAUUUUAAAGACAUGUACUGUCUAUAAUGGUACUUUCUUCUCAGUUGGGAACUAUUUAGGAGAGAUCUGUGCUAGAGGAGACAGUUUUCAGCUAGGACAUGCAAAUUCAAGAAAGGUCCAGUGCCAUAGCGUCUACAAGACGUCUUGUAGAGAAGCAAGCAGACUCAUUUCCUAUAGCUUCUGGGCAGUUCUGGCAUUGCAUGUGUGUUUCAGAUCUCUUCCGGAGAAGCAGUGUACUGAAUAAGAUCGAACAUGGAAAAUGGAAAGGAAGAGUGGGCAGAGAAGAAGGAGCUAAAGAACUUUUAAUAAAGAAAGUAUCAUCUACUUUAUAAUAGAUUAAAAAAAAACUUUUCGAUCCUAUCUGAUUCCUGUCCUAUCAGAGAAAUCCCUAAAAUGAACAAAUUUGAGGAGAAUGACAAACAUCCAUCUGCCUUAAAUUAUCUUCCAAAUUUCUGCCACUCCCAGCUUCAAAGCCACUCCUUUGGCAAGUCAUUGAUUCAGCCUUAGAAGAUCACUGUUAAAAGCCUUCCCUGAAGGGAAAAUCAUGCUCGUUAAUGAAUGAAUCUAAGCUGGGUAACAUACUCUUCCAGUAGGCAAGUGAAAGCUGGGGGAAUAUGAGUCCAAGCAAGGGGACUGAGAUGGGGAAAUAGAGGAGGUAACUUUUUCCUUGUAAGAUGUGGGUGGAAAGGAAAGAUGUUGAGAUCUUUGCUUGUUUCCCACUUUCAUCUAAACUCUCAUCAUGCUGUUUGCUGAAUUAUCAACCACCAAUUAGUGGUAGGUUUUAGGCCAAGCCAGGUAACUUCUUUGAACUUCAGUUUCCUCAAAAUGAUUGCUUAAGAUCAGCACUUCCAAAGGAGGACCUGUAAGGAAAAACACUGGUUCUGUGGGAUAUUACAGGAAAAAAAAAACAGUGGAUUAAAAAUGUUUUUGUUUUUUGAGUUGCAGGACUUUUAGAACAUUUAGUAACUGAAUGUUCACUCUAUAUAUCUGAAAGAAGGUGUGAUAUAUAAUAUUCAGUGAUUCCCAGACCUAUUUGACAGUGAUACUCAUUUUGAGGGUUCAUCUUGAGGGUCAGUGUUUUCUGAACACAAAAUAUUGGACUAUCUGGUGUCUGACGUCCUUCUAUGUUUUAAAUUCUGUGAAUGUACAAUUAGUUUGUCUCUCCUCCUAUUUCUUUCCUAGCCAGCCCCCUUGCCUCUUACCUAGAACUGUUUUUGUGUUGUGUGUAAACCAUUUGAUCAACAAUGUACUCUGUUAGAAAAUCUCUGCAUCUACUUUAAGAGAAGUGCAUGUUGAGAUAGUGCAAAUCUGCAAGCUAUGCACUUUUCCCUUUUAUUUUUAUAUUUUAGACUACAUUAAGUCAAAGGCAGUCAAAAAGCAAACAAUAAAUUCCCCAAGUGCUGUACACCCUGCCCAAUAUCCUAAUAAAAAUAUUGAAACAUUUAUACUAAUAGAGGGGAUAAUAUUUCAGAAAAGAAUAAUUUACAAAAGACCCAGGUUUUAUUCCGACAGAGGCGUUUCUAAGCAAAGCAGGGCAAUUAAUCAUAGAGCUGUAACAUAAAGAUGAAAAGAUGAAUACUGAAUAUAUAGAAAAUGUGCGCUAUUCUUCCCUUCAUCUUUAGAAUUACAAAAGAUGUUUAUCACCCCUUGCCUUACCAACACCAAUCUUGGAUUUUUUAUUUGGCUUCUGCACCAGAUUCACCCUUGACUUGAUGAGGAGCAGGUAAAAGCUGAAGUGCUUUGUGGGAGUGGGUGCGGGAGUGGAGGAAGGUAUAGACAUCCAGGAUGUAGGAUGGCUGUGUCUGAAUUAGACCUCCUCCUACAAAAAUAGCUCCUCUUCCAGAUGUUUUUUAAAGUGAGGGAAUACAAGGUGGUCAUCUGUAAUCUCUUGAGUCAGAAAGAGAAAGAGGCAGGCAUAGUGUCUUGUGCCUAUAGUCCACCUACUUGGCAGGCUGAGGCAGGAGUAUGGAUUGAGUCCAGGAGUUUGGGGCUGCAGUGUGCUGUGACUGCACCUGUAAAUAGUCAUUGCAUUCUAGCCUGAGCAACACAGUGAGACUCCAUCUUUAAAAAAAAUAAAAAGAGAGUAAGGAUUCUCACUGAGACACCCCCCGACCCCAUCUCUGAAAAAAGAAUGAAUAAAGAGUAAGGAUUCACACUGACUAUUUUUCAUAUACUUAUUGUUGCAUGUCGUGAAUUCUCUGAAAGUAAAAUGAUCUGAAUAUCUACAGGUAACCUACAGGUAAUCUAUAGCAGACAUCUUACUGUAGGCUAUGUGUUUGGUUUGAUUGUCUAUGGUCCACCCUUAAUUUAAAUUUUUUUUUUUUUUUUUUGAGACGGAGCCUCGCUUUGUUGCCCAGGCUGGAGUGCAGUGGCGCGAUCUCAGGUCACUGCAAGCUCUGCCUCCUGGGUUCAUGCCAUUCCCUGGCCUCAGCCUCCCGAGUAGCUGGGACUACAGGCACCUGCCACCACACCUGGCUAUUUUUUUUUUUUUUUGUAUUUUUUAGUAGAGACAGGGUUUCACCAUGUUAGCCAGGACAGUUUUGAUCUCCUGACAUUGUGAUCCACCCACCUCGGCCUCCCAAAGUGCUGGGAUUACAGGUGGGAGCCAACGCACCCGGCCUUAAUUUAAAUUUUUAAGAAUAUUUGUCAAAUUUUCUGGUAUUUGAAUUCAAGCUUACCUCUGAUGAAACAUUAAUAUUUCUAUUUAGUUUUCCUUGUCUUGUUUAAAAAAUUGGAAUUUGUUGUGUGCAUUUGAUUAUGUAUAUUUUAAAACUCCAAAUUGCAUUUUGAAAUUUGGCAGACAACUGAUAACUGUAUUUUUCUCAAAUAUAUAAAAGAUAUAUUAACAAUAUUAGCUUUGCUCUGAGGUCUCGUAGGUCUGUAGCCUCCUUGAGUUGCCUUAGUGAGGCUUCCAAACUGCACCGUGCUCCAGUUUUUGAAUUAAACUCUUCCAUUUUUAGAGGCCACCUUUACUAUUCUCCUGAACAUAUAAAUGAUGCCUUAGUUUACUAGUCUCAAGCCCUGGCAGAGAAUAGAUGUCAAGUAGAUAUUUGAUGAGCAGACUCUCCCUACUUGAUCAGUGUUUCUUGAAUAAAUGAAUAAAUUGUUAAUGAUAAGUGCUUAUUAUAAUUGUCACCACUUUUAUUCCAGUAAUGUAGCCACUGCCUGGCAUCUAAUACUAUUUUUUAAAAACAGUUAAAAAAUAUUUUUUUUUGUAACUCACAAACUUGAUGUUAAUUCGUAUUUAAUGUUUGUUUUUCUAUUUAAAAAAAUGCAUAAAGUUAAAAUUAUUGUACAUAAAAGUUUUUACACAGAUUUCACAAAGCUGAACACAUGUGUCUGUGCAAUUGGUUCUGUACUGCAGCAGCUCAAUGAACUUGGGAGAGACCUGAGUCCUCUCACGUAGGACUGAGUUGCUCUUUAUGGGACUGAACAUAAGUGCCAUAAAACCACUUGGUAGGGUUUGUUUUGGCAUGUUACAGCAUUUCCCCUCGGGAAUGCUCAAACAUUUUAUGGAUGGAGGAUUUCCAUAAAGUCUUCUACAUAACCUUCAAGUCAUCUUGUGUGAAAAAGAACUUAGUUUGCAUUUGUUCUGUAGAUAAUUGUUGAUGUUUUAUAGGUAACACUCUAGAUGUGUAGAAAGAUUGAGGCUUUCCAGGCACUUCUCAGACUUACUGACUAGUAAGUCUCUGUUAUUAAAAACUAGUUUUGUUUUUUGUUUUUUGAGACGGAGUCUUGCUCUGUCACCCAGGCUGGAGUGCAGUGGCGUGAUCUCGGCUCACUGCAACCUCCGCCUCCCGGGUUCUAGCGGUUCUCCUGCCUCAGCCUCCCAAGUAGCUGGGACUACAGGCAAGUGCCACCACGCCCAGCUAAUUUUUGUAUUUUUAGUAGAGACGGGGUUUCACCAUGUUGGCCAGGAUGGUCUUGAUCUCUUCACCUUAUGAUCCGCCCGCCUUGGCCUCCCAAAGUUCUGGAAUUACAGGCGUGAGCCACUGCGCCCUGCCUAAAAACUAGUUGUUUUUCUCACAAUUCUGGAAGCUUGGCAGUCAGAGGUCAAGGUGCUGGCAGGUCUGGUGUCUGGUGACUUGCAGAUGGUGGCCUUCUUACUGUAUUCUUACAUGGGGUGGGGUUGGAGGGGAAGGUGAGAGAAGAGAGGGCGAGAGAGAGAAGAAGAAGAGAAAGAGGAGGAGGAGGUGGAGGAAGAAGAGAGAAGAGAGAGAAGCAAGUUCUUCUAUGUCUCAUUAAGAGCACUAAUGCUAUUCAAGAGAGCCCCACCAUCAUGAUCUCCCAAAGGUCCCAUCUCCAAAUACUGUCGCAUCACAUUGGGGUUUAGGGUUUCAGUGUAUGAAUUUUGGGGGACACAAACAUUCAUUUUAUGGUACGUAUCAUUCUUUUUUAGGUUGGGCAGGGAACAGGCUCCUCAUCUCUCUCUGGCGUUCCCCCUAUUUUCCCCAAUUCCCUAACAAUUUGACCAAAGCCAUGGCCAACAUCAUCACUUGACAAAAUGGAAUUGAUUUGUUAAAGCGCUUGUUUAUUUUAAGAAUCAACCUAAAGGAAAAAGAAUUCAAGUUACUUAUUUUGGGGUCUGGAUUGAAAUUUUAUUUGCUGUAAUUUUAUCCCCAAAAUGACAGAUUCCUUUUUCAUAUUUUUUGAGUGGGUAUUUGUGUCAUUUUUUUGGCAGCACUUAAGAAACUAUCUCUUAUUGGUGAUUUUGAGAAUUGUUCAUACUUGAACAGAGAUUAUGAGCUUAAGUUUAAAUAGCUUUGAAAUCUUUAAAAAAUAGUUACAUCUUUUAAUUGCAUGAACACUGUCUAUAUUUAACAUGUCCAACUAUUUAAAUGACCUAAUAUUUUAUAUUUGCCAAUGCAAGCAUAGCAACUGUCAGGCAACAAGUACUUUUUUUCUGGGCCCUACCCAGGGAUAUUAAAAAAUAGAGUGGAGCUGGGCGUGGUGGCUCAAGCCUGUAAUCCCAGCAUUUUGGGAGGCCGAGGCAGGUGGAUCACCUGAGGUCAGGAGUUCAAGACCAGUCUGGCCAACAUUGCGAAACCCUGACUCUACUAAAAAUACAAAAAAAAAAAAAAAAAAAAAAAAGAGUGGAAGACACAGCAACUGUUCUCAUGGAACUUGGCUUCUCUCCCUGUCUCUCUCUUUAAAUACCCAAGGGCCAACUUGUGCCAAUCAUAGUUCUGGGUGGAAAUACAAUAAUAAAUGAAAUGGAUAAAAGUCUCUAGGGAUAAAGCAGUGAACAAAAACCACAAAAAAUUCCUGUCCUGGUAGAGCUUACAUUCUACAGGAAUAGAGGCAGAAAAUAAGGAAAUAAAUAAGAAAUGUGCAGUAUGUUAGGCGGUGGUAAGUGCUAUGGAGAAACUAAAGCGAGGAAGGGGAGAGGAAGUACAGGGGUGGGUGGGAGGCAGCUGGUACCUUUAACUGUGGUUGUCAUGGAUGACUCCACUGUGAAGGUAUCACAUGAGCACCUGGACCAGCUAAGGGAGAGAGCCCUGAGGACCUCUGUGGGAAGAGCCCUCCAGGCAGAAAUGCAAAAGUGCUGUGAUGGCCUCAUGCCUGGCUUGCCCUCCAAGAAGGCAGGUAGAGCAAGCCAGGGGGAGUGUAGUAAAAAGUCAAAGAUGUACAGGGCAGGCUGUCCAACAUGCAAAGCCUUAGAGGUUAUCACACUAUGUUGAUUCUUCCCCCACUCUCUUCCUUCCUUCUUUGUGAGUUGGGGAGCCAUUAGAAAAUUCUGCACUGAGGAAUGACCUGAUUAAAUGAUUUUAAAGAUCACUGGUUACUGUGAGAAUAAAUAUAGGAAGGCAAGGUUGGAAAGAGGGAGACUAAAUAAGAGGCUGUUGUAGCAGUCCAGGUGUUGGCUUAGAUCUGGGUGGUUGCAGUGGAGAUGCUGAAAAAGGGCAUUCUUUGUCUAUUUGGAAAGAGUGGAGGAGAGGAUCUCAGAAGGAUAGGAUGUGGAGUAUAAGUGAGAAAGCAGUGUCAAGCAUGCUUCUAAGGUUUGGGACCUGAUAACUGGAAGGGUGGGGCUGUCAUUUACUGAGAUACAAAGACUGAAGAGUAACAGAUUUGGAAGAGGAUCAUGUCAGGUGUGCACACCUUAGAUUUGAGACACCUAUUAGGCUUCUAAAUGGAGAAAUGGAGUAGGAGGUUGGGAAUAUGAAUAUUAAUUCAGGGGAGACAUCUGGGCUGAAGAUGUAAUGAUGGGAGCUUCAUGAUCUCAGUAAAAGCCAUAAAAGGGGAGCAAAUCCUCGAGAGUGAGGAGAUGAGAUCAGUCUGUCAGAGACAGAGUGAAGACAAUGAAGUUGCAGUUGUGUGCUCCAUUAUUAUUUGCUGUAGGUACAGAGAGAAGUAGGAAUUUGUGGGCUAGAAAACUGAAGCAACUUUCAUGAAAAGUGUGGGACUUGGACUGGUCCUUGCAAGUGGUUAGGAUUUGGAGGGUUAGAGAAAAUGAGGAGAGGGCAUUUUGGUUAAAAGUUACCAGAAUUAAACACAGUGCAAUAUGAGGUAGUAAGGGAAAACACACCAAAGUCAUGAUGGGAUUUUCUCAUGUGUGGAAGCGGUAAUACUUGAAGAUUUUGUUCAGUCUGUUUCCAAGGAUCAUGAUAUGCAAAUGAUAAAGAGACUUGGGUCCCAUUAAAUUUUUUAACAUUUCCCAAUACUUUGCUAACAGCUUUUCCUCCUUACCCUUGCAGCUGGUGCUGCCUUAUAUUUUGUAGUAACUUGAAACUGACAUGUGGGGAAUUUUAAGUACAUAUGUUAUCAAAACAUGUUUCACAGACUUUAUAGACUAUCAGGAGGUCAUCUUGUCUUUCAAAAAGCAGCCUGGAAUUUGAAUUUAGUUCCUCUUAUAAUUUCAUGCUCCAAAGUAACUAUAUGAGAAAUUUAAAAUUUAUUAGCAACUUUCUCUUGUUCUUAGAUUUUAGAGAGAUGGCAAUUUCAUUAAACCUGAAAAAAAAAUAUAUAUGCUAUGUUACCUAGAGGCAGAUUAUUGAAUAACUUUACUUGCCUGGUGAUAAAUCUAAGGUGCAUGAGUAUUUUAACGCUUUCCCAGCAACUUUGGGGUUACAUUUUUAAAAAGGAAAAAAAUCAACAACCCUGCAUUCCUUUUUGAUACAAAGUAACAAAGCAAAAAUGAACCUCAUAAAAGAAUACAAAGGAUGCCAGCUUCAGAACAAAUGGUUAGAGACAUUGUGCCUUUUGUCCCCUCUCCCCACUUUUUCCUAGAAUCUAUGUAAGAAUCAGGUAUUGUUUUUAUUCUGUCAAAGGUUUUCAUGGAGUUGCAAAAGCUAAGGACUUUGGCAGAACUCUCUGAAGUAAGAGCAAAUUAUACAUUUCGUUGUUCAUUUUCCUUAAAGAAUGCCUUUAAAAUAAUGUGGUGUUAAUUGUUUGGCAUAACCAGGUGUGACAUUCCAUAUGCCCAUUUGUUCUUUGGGUUUCAAGGAGGUUCAGAGUACAACUCCUGCAGGACUUGACAGUUUAUCUGUGUCCCUUGAAUCCUGCAGGUGUUGGCUGGAGAGUAGUAAGCAGUUAGUGGCAAAGGGGUUUAUAAAGAAACCCUGUGGACUCUCUAGUGCUGUCCAGUAGAAUUUUCUAUCCUAUUCUUGGUGACAGGAAUAUUCUAUGUAUGUACUUUCCAAUACGUGGGUAGAUGCUACCCAUACUGGCUACUGAGUACUUGAAGUGUGGUUAGUACAGUUGAGGAACGAAUUUUAAGUUGAUUUCAUUUUAAUUAAAUGCAAGUAGCCACAUGUAGUUAGUGUCUCCUGUGCACUUGUUUUUAUUCUGUAAAUAAAAUAGUGACUGCCCAGCCAAAGCUAACAAUUCAUCUUGGGCUUUCUGGAGCACAGAGUGGACAGAUGCCCACACUACCCUUGCCGGGGCCUUUCUGCCAUCCUGGUGAGUGUCCACAGGCAGAUCUUUCACACAGGGACAUGGCACCCCUGCUUAUUUCCAGGAACUGGACGGUAUACAGGACUUUUUGAAAUGCCUCCCUCUUGUCCUUCCCAGAAGUGGGGAGAAGGAAUAAGGAAAAGCAGAAUGACAUUAGAUGAGGUGAGGUCAUUUUUAUGGUCUUAAAGACCUUUUUCUCACAGAGAUAUUUUAAAAAAUAGCCUAGGCUGGGUAUGGUGGCUCACGCCUGUAAUCCCAGCACUUUGGGAGACCGUACAGGUGGAUCACUUGAAGCCAGAAGUUCGAGACCAACUUGGCCAACAUGGUGAAACCCUGCGUCUAAUAAAAAUACAAAAAUUAAAUGGGUGUGGUGGUGCACACCUGCAAUCCCAGCUACUCGGGAGGCUGAGGCAUGAGAAUCCCUUGAACCUGGGAGGUGGAGGUUGCAUUGAGCUGAGAUCAUGCCACUGCACUCCAGCCUGGGUGACAGAGUGAGACUCCAUCUAAAAAAAAAAAAAAAAAAAAAAAGAAAGAAAACAAGCCUAUUUGAGUAUUUUAUUACUGACUGAGAAUUAUCCUGGGCCGUAGAUGUUAGAGGCAGCAUUAGUACAUACUGAUCUUGCUGGUGUCUUGAAAGUGAGAAUUCUGUGAAGAACCAAAUUUCAUACCUGGAGGAAGAUUGCGUGUUCAUAAGGAAUAUUCUCUAGAUUAUUAUUUUAAAAAUUUAAAAGUGGAUUAUUGAAGGUCUACCAUGCACCUUCACGUAAAUACAAAAUGUGUAUGUAUUGUUCCAGGAAGGGGGUUAUUAAAGAAAGGCAUAGAUAGCACAGGACAUAAAAAUGAUGAAGAUUGGGUCACUGUAAGCCAAGGAAGGGCUGAGUGUGUGACAAAGACAGGCGCUGGGCCCCACCCCAGGAUUCUCCAGAAGGAUGUUGCUGUUAUGGAAGUCCUGGUUAAAAUCACACUCCGGGAGCAUGGUAGGUGGUGCAGGAUAAAGGAGGUCUUUUGUCUCUCGGUGGUCAGUUUUUACACUGAAGAAGUUGGCCACAGUCUUACUGCUGCUGUGGUGAGCUGCCCCUGCCCUGCGCCAGUAUCAGAAGCUGUCCCAGUUGAAUUUGCUGAGAAAGGUGUUUAAAAAGAUUUGUUGGUUGAUAUUUCUGUGGACAUUCUGCCACUCUCACUUGUAAAACUAAAUGGAGCUUAUGUGCCAGGGACCAUGCUUCACUUGCCAUCUAAAUGAGGAGGAAAAAAAUGUGUACAUGGAAGAAGAAAACUAACGAUAAAAAAUGCUAUAAGGUAGAUCCCCAAUGAGUGGUGCAGACAGUAACUGCCAUAUCCGAUAGUUGUCUUCAAAUGCAUAAAGGGCUGGCAGGUGGAAGAGGUGUUAGACUUACUCUCUGGGGCUCCGGAAGGCAAAACUGGUGGUAUUUCUUUUUAAUUAAAAAAAUGAUUUUUGAAGGCCUAUUUAUGUAGAGUACUCUGGGGAGAGAGAAUGAUUUAGGAGAGGACAGCAUGUUCAGGAUAUGGAGAUGUGACAGUGGCUGCAAGUUACAGGGAAGUUCAUUCCAGUGAAUAGAAGGGAGAGCUUCAGAAAACACAACAGGCUGCUGUGAGGAGGUUAUCCCCCUUCAUCGGAGGUGUUCACAAAGAGACCUUGCCUACUGGCUGGGAAAGGGGAUUCAUACUGGUAGAGCAGGGGUCAGUCAAAUCUGGGUGGCUACCUCCUUUUGUAAAUGAAGUUUUGUUAGAACUCAGCCAUUGCCCAUUUGUGUACGUAUCCUGCAUGGUUGGUUUUGCACUACAAUGGUAAAAGUGUGUAAUUGGGACAGAGAUCACUUGUCCCUCAAAGCCUAAAAUAUUUGUUAUCUGGCCCUUUAUAGAAAAAGUUUGCUGGGCCCUACAUAGGAUUGGAUUUAGAGAUAUGUAAAAUCCUUUUUAAUUUUCUGGUUGUAAGGGAUUCAGAAAAGAAGACAAAAGCCUUGUGGGAAGUCUGAAGAAGGUUUCUUGCAAGAUGUGAACUUUCGGUUGGGCCUUAAAAGAAAACGCUUGCUGGUCCUGGCAGAGGAGGCCUGUCCACAUGGAACACUUGAGCAGAUCUCAAGAGGACUGCAUCUCUGGUCCUUGAAUGCAGUGUACAGACUCAUUCCAGCAUCCAUGCAUUCAUUCAUGCAUUGUGACUCCAGCAUAUUGCAGGCCAAUGUAGUCAUCUACAAACACUUCUUGGCCUGCUCUUGGUAAAGUAAGCACAAAUUCUGGCAUGAGCUGUUGGCAUUUUGUUACUAACUUUGCCAGAGUGAAAAUGCUCGUGAAGUUCAAUGUUUAUCAUUGAGUUUUACAGAGUUAUUUUAUUUUAAGUAUAAUUGUCUCACCUAGAGACAACUUAGAAUUUAUUUAUAUAUUCUGCUUAAUUGUAGGAUGUAAGAAAUGAUGGUUCCAAAACGAAAACCUCACUGUAUUUGUAGGAGAUGCAACUCGGAGUGUUAAGGAUAGGAUGAUGCACAUUACUAUUCAUGCCUUUUUAAUUGAUUAGCCUUUAAGGCUUCUGCAAGCCUUUAAAAGUUGUUUUGUCAACAUUAGACCAGCUGCUGUGUAAUUAUGGUAGCUCUUCUUGCAGUUAAAUUCCUUUAAUAACGUGUUCAAUCUGCCGAUGCCAAAGUGCUUUGAACCUGUGAUAUAUACUAUGGAGAGCUUUUGUUUUUACUUACAGAUGGUCGGUGUCAUUUUCUGGGCAACUCUAGAAUUUUCACAGAAAUUUUAAAGAUGAAUUACUUGAAAAUGGAAGGCAAAUGAAUUUGAACAUCAGGUUACUCCUCCCCCUAUAAAAUUUGUUCAUAUGUGACUUGAAUUUUGAACUUGGCUCAUAACAACAUAAAUGUGCUCAUUAAAAAAAAAAAUUCCACCUUGAAACCUUUUUAAGGCUCUUUUCUCUGACUCUCCAGCUUGUAAAUUAAAUCAAAUCUUUCUGGCACCAGAGAGAUGAUGGUGGAAACAGUGGGCCUGUAACAAAGAUCACUUGUUAAUGAGGAGCCACAAAAGGGUGGUUCUGCCUUCCAUUCAGGGGCUGAAACUUCACUCAGAAAACUGAGUGUGAAUUUAGCAGUGUGUGAAGUCUGGCAUGAGAACAUAUAACUAGUGAUAGGGUCUGGUGUCAGAAAGAUACAAACAGAAGAUCCUGUGUUUGUCUCCUCCCAGAUUCACCUGUCCUUCCUCCCGCAUUGGGUUGUACUGGUGGAUAAGGCAUGAGAGGUGGGAGCAGUGAUGAUGGUGGCUGUAGAGGCUGCCCCUGUUAGUUCAGGCCAUUUUGGUGGCUUCCUUCCUAUAGCCAUUUUUUUCCCUCCAAGAUGGAGUCUUGCUCUGUGACCCAGGCUGGAGUGCAGUGUCACGAUCUCAGCUCACGGCAACUUCUGUCUCCUGAGUUGAAGCAAUUCUCCUGCCUCAGCCUCCUGAGUAGCUGGGAUUACAGGUGCAUGCCACCACACCCGGCUAAUUUUUGUAUUUUUAGUAGAGACGGGGUUUUACCAUGUUGGCCAGGCUGGUCUCAAACUCCUGACCUCGUGAUCUGCCCACCUCAGCCUCCCAAAGUGCUGGCAUUACAGGCAUGAACCACCGCACCUGGCCUCCUAUAGCAUUUUAAAAGGCAAACCAUUCAAAACAGAGGCACAGAGCAUCAACACAUGAAGGAAUAAGAGAUUAGACCAAGCUACAGCAGCUUUCUAUGGCCCCAUUAUUUAAUUUGUAUUAAGGAAUGCACCUGUGUUGUUGGAAAACCAUGAGACGAGUCCAUCAACCACCUGCUCACCUUUUCUUUUCACUGUACAGCAUAAGGGGGCUUGGAAUGCAAUUAACCUUAUACAUUGUGAAAAAGCCGACAUGCUUCAAGCUUGAAUAGAAGUUCAAGAAUAUUAAUGACCUGCAAAAUUUGAAGAAGCAGCUAACCUUGGCGAUAUUGGCUUACGUAAUGGUAGGGCUAGCCAAAAAUUGUGCCUCCUGUACUCACUCACAAUGUGCAGAUUUGUUUGCCUUGAAAGCUCGUGAGCCCUGAGAAUUGGGGCAUUUAAGAGUUUGAGGAACCAUAGACUUAUGAGCAUAGAGCACUUGUGGUGUUAUGAAGUAGCCACUAGACACUCAAAUAGAGAAAACUAGAAUUUAUUUAAUUAAAAGUUGUUUAAUUAAUUAUAUUUUUCCUAUGGGAUAAAACUGUUCCUGGUAAAUGGCUUAAUCUUUUCAAAGUUACAUUAAAUGUUAGUCUGGAGUGUUUUUAAUAUUGCAGGCUCAUAGAGUUGUGUAUCAAGAUGUGCCCAAGAGAACUACCAUCAGUCUCAGCAUUAUAUUUCUAAAUACCAAAACUUGCUAGUGUCAGUAGAAGAAUACAUCUUUUUGGUAACAUCACCUUUUGCUAAAAUGCAUAGUUUACACUGAUAUGAUUGGAAUUAAAUCAGCCUCAGUUGUCAGUUCUAAUCAGCUGCAUGAGACAUGGUCUUCAAUUAAUCUUAUCUCAUAAACAUUAGCAUUUUAAAUACUUUGUCAGAGUCUUGCAUACACUUUUCGAAAAUUAGAAACUUUCAGAACUUCUUUGAGGACUUCAAAAUUGUUUUUGAUACCCUUCCAAAAUAAUCUUAUGUUAUCUUGAGAUUGCAUUGAAUCAGAGAGGAGAUGUUGGCUUUAAGACCCGAUAGUCAUAAACCUACAUACAUAUAUAUGCACAUAUAUCCACAUAUAUGAGUAAUCAGCUCCCAAGGAACCUAGUGGUCAGCAAGACAAGGGACUUGUGUAUACUCAGAUGGCCAAAUGUCAUGGAGGUCUUUAUUUCUCAAACUAGUCAUCCCCUUAACUCUCCUAUUACGUUCAAAGGUACCCAGGAAUAAAAUCUUUUUAUUUUUCUUAUCAAGUAUGUAGAAUCUUGUUUGUAAGCAGCAAAUACCUGGCUCAAAUUAACUUAGGAACAUUAAUCUCAUGUAUGGGCCAGAAUGUGUCUUUCUCUUUCACUUGACUUACUCUCUGUGGACUCUGUGAGGAUUGGCCUUUGCACUCUGGGUCUGUGUGCUUGCCUAACAGUAAAUUUUUAUGGCGAUGAACUGUGCCACCCCUCUGUUAUGUUAUUAAGUGUAAAAUAAAUUGAAAGAAGAGUUAAAUAGUCAAAAUGCUGGAAGAACAGGGCAAUAGCAGGGACUUGAGAGCAUUUAAUACUCUUUUCCCACUUUUUUUUUUUUUUCCUAUUACCUUACUGAUUUCAUUCUUUCUUAAUGCAAAACAAGUAUGCAAACAAGGUGGGAGUGAUGUCCUCAGAUGCUGCUGAAAUGUACACAUCUCAUAGUUUAUGCCAGCGUUUAGGACUGACUCAUGCUUUCUCCAGUACCAGACUCAACAAUCCUAGGGAAGAAAGCUCAUUGGCCUAUCUUGGGACAGAUAUCAACAUGGACCAAUAAGUUUUGGCAGGAGGUAGGACCACAUUGUACAAAGUUGUCAUUGGUGACCCCUUUUCUAUGUAUUAGUAAAAGAAAAAUCACUGUGGGCUGGAGAAGCUUCAAACACACGAGAUGUUUUCCUUCCCUACAUGGACACAUCACCUCAGUCUUCCCAAGUAUGGCUACUGGCCUCUUCUGGAUGUCUUCUUUUUCCCCAUUACCUCUAGCCUGAGUGCCAUUUCUUUUAAUGAUUUGGUAAAGAACUUGGGGCAAGACAUAUUGUAGACAGGAGGAGAAUUUCUGGGUUGGUGAUUUAGAGCAGAUCUCUUCUGAUCCUUUCCCCUGAGCCCAGUACCCCUCAUUUACUUUUUGGCAUGCAGGAGGAAGUGGCAACUCAGGAGAAGGCAGAUGGAAAGGUUAAAUGGUGAAGCUCACAAUCUGCUUGGCCAAGGAAAUAAUGCCCUUUUCUUAAAGGCUAAAUGUUUUUUCAGGAUGAGUGGAUCAGUGGAGUCCAAAUAUUCUUGUCUACUGUAGGAGAUAUUUGAUUCUUUAUGUAUGUAUAACAUAUGUGUAAUAGUUGUAGAUAAAGCAAUUUUGAUUUUUCUUUGUUUACUGAUUUGUUUUCAUUAUCCAAAUUCACUUGUAUGUACUUUUAGGCUGAGAAAGUUUUCCAAACCAUUUUAACAUGCAACUCUUCAAAAAUUUACUGGGAUUCUUUGUAUUUGCUUAAAUAGGAGCCAUUCUGUGUUUUUUCCCCAAGUUAAUGGUGCUAACUCACUUAAUGUUCUAAUUCUGACAGCCAUUCAGUAAUAAUGCAUUUCCAGAGGAGUUGCAGUAGAAUUUUAAGCCUUGUAUUUUUGGCUCCUACUUAGUUAUCUACCCUGAUUGGCAUUUAACCAUUGAAUUAGAUUUUUCUUCUACUGAAGAGAGCUUUAUGAGCUUUAACUUCAAGUGUCUGUGUCACAGUGUGAUUUGUUUGCAUUAUGAUUGACACUGAGCAAGCACUUUUUGCAGGAAAAGGCAUUGUCUUUUAGGAUUGAGGGAGGAUUUGGACACAUAGUCUCCUGACACUUUUUUCCAGGGUUCCAUUUAAUAGUUGUGCACAUCAAUAACAAUCUCACCUGGCACAUGUUAACAUGGUUACUUUAUUUUUGCAAUCAGUAAUGAUCAUAUUCCCUGAGAGCUGUUUCUCUGGGCCUGUUGACUGAUAUGGCCAUAAAUAUAUCCCCAAAGGCUAAAACUGUACCUGUUUCAGCACAGAUGAAAUAAAAAUAAAUGUCCCACUGUUUUAGUAUUACAAAUUAUAAUCUCACUACAGCAUGAACUUUAAGGUGGUGAUAGUUCAAUUUCUGCUCUUUGUUUUUGACAUGAUGGUAGAAUAAAUACAAUUUUAAAACAUUUUAUUCAAUUAAUUUUCAGUGACCAUUUUGUGUGCCUGGUUCAUUCUGUGCUCUCUAAAUCAUGAAAUACAUUUCUUUCUUUCUUUUCUUUGCUUUUUUUUUUUUUUUUUUAAGACAGAACCUCACUCUGUUGCCCAGGCUGGAGUGCAGUGGCACAAUUUCGGCUCAUUUCAACCUCCACCUUCCAGGUUCAAGCGAUUCUUCUGCCUCAGCCUCCUGAGUAGCUGGGAUUACAAGCGUGUGCCACCAUGCCUGGCUAAUUCUUGGAUUUUUAGUAGAGAUAGGGUUUUACCAUGUUGUCCAGGCUGGUCUUGAUCUCCUGACCUCAGGUGAUCCGCCCGCUUCGGCCUCCCAGAGUGCUGGGAUUACAGGCAUGAGCCACUGCGCCCGGCUGAAAUACAUUAUAUUUCAAAAAUAGUACUACCUUUAGAAGUUCUUACCUUUAAUUGUUAAUAGUGAAUAAACAAAAUAAUGUUUUCUGGACCUAUAAAUGGAUUUUGAAGAUAUCCUUGCCUUAAAGAGACCAAAUAAUAUACUUGCUGUUUCUUCCUAUUAUAUUAUCAUAUUCAUUCACUCAGUCAGCAAACAUCGAUUACUCUACCUCUGGGAACCUAAAACAUACUAGGGACGUAUAGACAAGUAACAAGUCUUUAAUAAAGAGUUAGAGAAAUCAUGACGUAAAGUACAAUGGGGACACAAAGAUAGGGACUGGCUGGUUGCAUUCAGGGAUUGCUUUAACUAGAAGAUAACACUUGAAGUAAGCCACUUAUGCUAACUGGGUGUGCCCAGAGAGGGCCAGAAAGAAGGCCAAAAGAAUGUGAAUCAAGUCCUAGAGCAUAAAGCGGCAUGGGCAAUUGGGGGAAGUUGUUUGUUUAAAUUUAGAGUCAAUGUGUAAGGGAGUGAGUAUCUAGAAGUGGGACACAAAAAAGGUGGGAUAGACCCUAAUCAGAGAUGAAUAUGCAAAUAUAUAUAUUUUCUAAAUAUAUAUAUAUAUUUGACUAGAAUUUGAAUUUUAUUCUAGAUAUUAGUAGUUUUCCAACGUUUUUGGUUUACAGUAUUAAAUUUAAGAGGAGGAUGAAUAUUCCUGUGAUUGUCAACUUGGGGAAGUACCAGAAUCUUGUUGGGUGGAGGACAGGGGCACAUUAAUAAUUUUAAAAACCCACAAGGUGAUUGUGAUAAGUCCUUGUGUCCUCUCCAUUGAGAAUUAUUGCUAUGGGCAGUGGAAACCACUGAGUUUUAAGUGGAGUCCUUAAUAUCAGUGACCCCAUUAAAGUACUAUCUCAAUUUAUUAUUCUUUAAAUAAAACAAUUGAAAAAUAUACUUACGUCCUCCAUCUCUAUGCUCCCAUGAUCCUCUAUGUAAUUUUUCAGUAUCAAAUUUUAAAAAAACUCAUUUGUUGUGCUGUUGGCACAAACAUAUUUUAAAGGAGUGUUUGGGAAUGGAACAUAAAACAGAAAUGGAAAAAAAAUUAACAUUAUAUAUGUCUGUCUUUGAUUUCCAUGACUGCACAUCUUUGAUUUCCAUGCAUGUCUUUGAUUUUCAUGACUCAGAGCUUUUCUGAGAUUCCUAUGGGGGUGUCCAGGCUAAUGGGAGAAGCAGCUGGAGGAGAGUAUGGCAGGCCGAGUGCCUGGCACACAGUAGGCACACAAUGAUUGCUAGUGUCUUUAGCUUCUCCUUUUAAACUUCAGCUCUUUAGUUGAAAUUUAGGAGCCACUGGAUUUUCUGUUAGUGGCUAAUGUCAAGAGUGGCUGAGAAAAAUGUUUGAAACUGAGGAGAAAAUAGUGUCUCAGAUAUUAGACACAUAUAAACAUUAGAAGGGAAUUUAAUGAUUGUCUCGUAUCCCAGCCUUCUGCUUCACAGUUGGUGAAACCAAGGCCCUGACUUGACAUCACUUGAGUGACUUGACAUCACAAGGCUAUUAAAUUACAGAAAAGGACCAGAAGCCAGGUCCUUUAAUUCCUUCAUGUCUCUCAGACAUGUAGAUGGCAUUUCUUCCUGUUUUUUCUUUUUCUUAGAGUUAACUCCAUGAAAGGUUCUAAUCAGCAUAUCUAAAACAUAGCCCUUCAUGAACUUCUUCCUCUUUCUCUACUUUUUGUAUCCCUCUAUUACUAGAAAGGGAUCCCAAUCCAGACCCCAAGAGAGGGUUCCUGGACCUCGUGCAGGAAAGAAUUUGUGGUAAGUUCAUAUUGUAAAGUGAAAGUAAGUUUAUUAAGGAAGAAAAUAAACAAAAGAAUGGCUGUUCCAUAGGCAGAGCAGCGGCAUGGGCUGCUCACCUGAGUAUACUUACAGUUACUUCUUGAUUAUAUGCUAAACAAGAGGUGGAUUAUUCAUGAGUUUUCUGGGAAAGAGGUAGGCAAUUCCUGGAACUGAGAGUUCCUGCCCAUUUUAGACCAUAUAAAGUAACUUCCUGAUGUUGCUAUGGCAUUUGUAAACUGUCAUGGUGCUGUUGGAAGUGUCUUUUAGCAUGCUAAUACAUUAUAAUUAGUGUAUAAUGAGCAGUGAGGACGACUGGAGGUCACUUUUGUCACCAUCUUGGCUUUGGUGGGUUUUGGCUAGCUUCUUUACCACAACUUGUUUAUCAGCAGGGGCUUUGUGACCUGUAUUUUGUACCAGCCUCCUAUCUCAUCCUGUGACUAAGAAUGCCUUAAUCUCCUGGGAAUGCAGCUCAGUAGGUCUCAGCCUUAUUUUUCCCAGCCCCUAUUCAAGAUGGAGUUGCUGUGGUUCAAAUGCCUCUGACACCUCAGUGGCAUCAACAUCUACCAUGCACUUGAGCUAGUCAUUUCAGCAUCAAUUUUGUCUCCAUCUUAUACAGUAUUCAGCUAGUCAUCGAGUCCUGUUGGUAUCACUUUGGAAAUGUCUCUCACAUCUAUCUUUGCUUCUAUUUCCUAUAUUACUUCCUUAAUUUAGUCUUUACUUGUUUUUUUUUUUUUCCCUCUGGACUAUUGAAGUAGCUUUUAAAUUGGGUUCUGCCUUCUGCAGUCCACUGUCUCCACUGCCUCUGGAGUUUUCUUUUUGAAAUAUAAAUCUCAAUGAUGGGUUCAGUAGCCUUCAGUGGCCUUUCAUUCUAUUGAAAAGUCCUUUUCUCUAGCUGUAGCCUUUCACAAUAUAGCUUUGAUGUCCCUUUUCAACAUUUUCUUCUGAUCAUUUUUCUACUCCCUUUAUCUGCCAGACUCUGAUCACACCAGCCCAUUCAAUGUUCCUAAUUUUUCAAUGUACUUUCCUGGGACACCCUUCAUCACCUCAGUUUGAGCACACAUCAGUGCUCAAUUCUAUGCAUGCGUAGGAAAAGAAAAGUUGUUUUCCUCUGUUCUUUAUAGUUCUUAGUUGGGGUGGACCCCUGUAACAAAAGACAGAUUAAGAUGAGAAAAACAAGUUUAUUAACAUGUAUAUUUCAAAUAUACAUGGGAGAUACCCAGAUAAAUGAGUAAAUCUCGAAAGGGUAGAUUUGAAUUCAGGCUUAAAUAUCAUCUUCAGCUAGAACAAAGAAAGCUGUUGGGGGAUACAGUUAUGGGAGGUAACCAGGAAAAGCGUGAGACACAAGGGUAAGAUUCCUUAUAUAGAUUUAAGUCAGUGCCUUCUCCAUUAAUACAAGUCUCUAGUGAUUUAGAGUCAUCUUUCCUGAUGCAGAGAGGGUGACACAGUUACAAAUAGAGAUUUCCUUUAUAGAUGUAAAUUUUCCUACAAAAGGGUAACUUCUACUCUGCUUUUAGAGCUUCUCCUGUAUUUUCAGUGUUCAAAAUAAUCAGCUUGAAAUAAUCUUUAUGCCAAAGAGGCAUACUUUGGGAUGGCGUAUUCUGGUCUCUUAAAUACACAUCACUUUCUUUGAGUCCUCCUUUCCUUUCUUGGUCGAGAUAAACAGAUGGAUCCUCUGUUACCCACAGAGCACUUUGUUUCUUCUCUAACCAUACUGAGUGCUGUAGUCUGAUGUGCAUGAGAAUUAAUUUUCUUUUUGAAUAUGUCUGUUUUAUUCAAUAGUUUAUGAAGUCCUUGAGCUCAGCAGUUGUAUCAAAUUCAUUUUUAUAUCCUUGGUACCUGUGGUAAAUUGAAUAAUGGUCCCCUGUAGAUUUGCAUCUUCUAAUCCUUGGAACCUGUCAGUAUGUUACCUUACAUGGUAAAAGGGAUUUCUUAGAUGUGGUUAAUUAAGGAUCCUGAGAUGGGGCUAUUAUCUUAUUAUCAUGGUGGAGAAAGGCAGGAGGGUUGGGGCAGAGAAGAUGAUGUGAUGAGAGAAGCAGGCAUAGAGAGGGGAUAGUCAGAAGAAGCAGAGGUUGCAAUGAUGUGCUUUGAAGGUAAAGGAAGGCACCAUGAGCCAAGGAGUGCAUGUAGCCUCUGGAAAAGGCAAGGAAGCUCAUUCUCCCUUAGAGCCUCCAUAAGGAAUGAAACUGUGCAGAUGCUUGAUUUUAGCCCAGUAAGACCCAUAUUGGACUUCUGACCUUCAGAACUUUGAGAUAACACAUUUGUGUAAGUUUCGAGCUACUAAUUUUGUGGUAAUUUGUUACAGCAGCAAUAGGAAACUAAUACAGUGGAGGAGAGGAAAAAUAUUUUUUUCUCUACCCAUUGUAGGUUUAUGGAUGAGGCCUCUAUGACAAAAAACAGAUUAACAAGAGAAAAGCAUACAAAUUUAUUUAAUAAAUUUUUAUGUGACAUGGGAGCCUUCAUAAGGAAAUUGAGACCCACAGAAAUGGGUAAACCUGAGUAUUUUUAGGCUAGGUUUGAUAACGAGUGGAUAGUUGUGGAGAAAUAUGAUGGGAUAAAAAGGGUAUAAUGUAAUAGGAAUAAAUUGAGGAGAACUUAGAAAGGUCUGUUUGUUCAGAUUCUGCCCAUGACUGUCUUAAUCCAUUUUGUGCUGCUACAACAGAAUGGCUGAGACUAGGCAACUUAUAAACAAUAUAAGUUUACUUGUUUCAUGGUUCCAGAGUCUGAGAAGUUAAAUAUCAAGGAUCUGGCAUCUGCUGGGGGCCUUUUUGCUACAUCAUCCCAUGGCAGAAGGUAGAAGGGAAGGAGAGUGCAUAUGAGAGGGUGAGAAGUGAAGGGGGCUAGAACUCAUUAUUUUCUUAGGAACGUACUCUUAUGAUAAAUAACCCACUCCCAAGAUAAUGACAUUAAUCCAUUCCGAGUCACCUCUUAAAGAUCCCACCUCUCAACACUGUUGCAUGGGAGAUUAAGUUUUCAACACGUGCAAUUUGGGGGAUACUUUCAACUCAAAACAGUGGCGCUUCAUCUUUAGCGACAAGGAUGUUCCUUUUGUCCUGGUAUAGGGAAGCACCUCUUAGAUGAGGGUCAAUGAUCUGCUUCAAGGGAAAGUUAGAAAGUCCUUCUUAAGUUUUUUGACCAGCUUCAGCGGAGAAGUAUGGGGGCAGGUCAGAGAGACCGUCCUGCUACUGAAGGAAUUUUUCUCACAUUCCUUUAGCCUUAAAGUUUCACUAUGCCAAGGUGCCAUAUUUUGGGUUAGUAUGUUCUGAACCCCAUCAACAGCACUUACAUGUAACAUGCAGUUGGGCUUAGUGUAUUUGCAUCUGACCUUGACUAAUCAAGAGAAUUGUUCUCGAUGCCCAUGAUGAUCAAAGCUAACAUUUAUUGAACCUUUUGCUGUGUGCCAGUCACUGUGGUCAACAUUUAUACUUGAUCUUCAUAAUCACUGUAUGGCACCAUUAUUAUCCCUAUUUGGCAGAUGAGAAAACUGAUGCACAAAGUGUUUUAAUAAUUUUCCCCCAAUCACACUACCCAAUAUGUGAUGGCACUGGGACUUGGAAGUGAGCAGUCUGGCUCCCAGGUCUGUGGCCACAGCGCUGUAUCCUGCUUAGUCAUGUUCUCAUGUCACAUAUAUGCAAUUUAUGUGUGCUGUCCUAGUGUGAUAUGUCGUGAAGAAAAUUGGAAGAGCUAGAUUUGAAUAUUGAUGCCUUCAGUAAUCAGUUGGCUCUGUAAAUGUGGGCAAGUCAGCUAACCUAGAUCUGUGUGCCUGUCUUUGUUAAAUCAUUCCUUUUCUGCUUACCUUAUGGGGUUAAUAUGAAGACUGAAUGAUAAAUCACAUGGGAAAGUGCUUUGAGAAACAGCAGGCACUACACAUAUGCUAUUUAUAAGUAUAUAUUUGGUUGAUGUAGAUCUUUUGCAGAUUUCCUCAUACCAGGAUUACCUGGCUGGUCUGAUUCAUUUGGUGAGUAGGGGCUUAAUAAUAUUUGGUAAAUGCAUUUGAUAAAAAUGCUCUUUUGCCCUCCUAGUUCUCAUUCUUAUAUUUUGGGUUGUUGACACUAAAAAUCUGAAAGCUCAGAAUUUAGUCUCCUUCAUAGAACUUUAUUUUCUUUCCUACUUUUAAAAAAAUGAGCCUUUCUUAUCUCACUCCUUAGCUAGUAUUUUUAUCUUGUAGCCCAUAGGAAGGUACGACUUAUAGAAGAUUUGCAAUGAUUUCAGCAGCUUUUCAGAAGGGCUUUGAGUGAACAGUUAAUCUCUUGAGAAUGCAAAGUCAUUUGUGGUGGAGAAUCUUAGGCCAGUGUUGAGUUGCAAAUCCUGGGGAGUCCUGACUCAAGAAGAUAGGGAAUUUAAAAAGAAAGCCAGUGAAAUACAUUUGAUUCUCUUUUUCCCUGUCCUGCCUUAGCCUGCAAUGUUACUUAUUCCUUUAAGAUGCUUUAAUUGCUAAUUGUCUGCUGUUUGAUUUUGAGGUUAGUUGAAAUCACCAGGAUGAUGGAAGGCCUGACCUGACCAGACCUGAAUUCAUUGGCAAAUUCUCAACUUUUUGAAAAAUUAAUGAGUUUUGGCUGAGAUGACACCUGACUUUUUACAGCAUCUUGUUUUGAUUUAUUGUUUCUUUUGUUUACUUGUCAGAUAUUCCCGCCCAUGACAUGGAUUUACAGAGUACAAUUUUUUUUUUUUUUUUUGCAUGUUCAAAGUCAAGCUAUCCUGAUUGGUGCAACAUACAGACAUAAAAUGAUACUUUGAGGGGCAUCCUUUUGGAUACAUUUUUGUUCCUCUCUCAUUGUUUCCCUGGGAUGAAUUCUUAGACAUAGAAUUACUCCAGGAAGGGUACCAACUUAAAACAUUAAAAUCAAACCAAACAAGAAAAAGAUACAUAUUAAUAGAUUGUAUUCCCUAAAGGCUGUACUAAUUAACACUCCCACCAGUAGUGUAUGAGAAUGCAUAUCUCACGGCAACUUUGUCAUUGUUCACUUACUCUGUAGCAUCUCUGGAGUACUCACAAUCUUCUAGGUUCAGACAUUUUUCAGAAGUUUUCAAAAUCACCCCAGGUGAUUUGAAGCUGAAACCACUGGUUUAGUUGAUAGGAGAAAAGCAUUCUCUCACUAUCUCUUAGUGGUUUGAAUCUCUCUCACUAUCCCCUUAAAAUAGAUCAGUCACUUUAGGUCAUUGGUGUGUUUUGCUACACAGGACAUACUAUUCCUAAUGAACAGCCCCUUCAUCACUCUAACACUCUUGAACCACUAAUUCACAGUAGUGUCACUUCUAGGCUUAUUAAUAUAAUCUUUUGCCCAUGCAAAGCUCUCCAAUGUUCAGAUAAUUCUGCUGGAUGAUGUUACCUUUCAACUGAACCACAUCAUCUUGUUGGCAAAGCACCUCAUGAAUACUAUCUCAUUUAACUAUUGCAGGGACCUUGGAAUUAGACAUUUCCAUUCUAUUUUUACAGAGAAAGGAAAAGGAACCCAAAUAAGUAGCUUUUCUCUAAGGUUGUGCAACUUAUAAUCACAUGUUAGGAACUGAAUCAAUGUAGGUCUUCUGAUUUCAAGUUCAGAGUUUCCAGUGUUGUGUCAGAACCUGUCUUUGGCUUUCGCUAGUUCUGCUGCUUUUUUAAUGCACAAAUGGAUCUGGUUAUUGGAUUGUUAUUAAGGAUUUUUUUUUCAGUGUCUGCAUUUCUUACGCUUAUUUUCUUCUCUGUGUGCUCAUUUAGAAUUCUACAUAUUUACAGCUGUGUUUCUCAACGUUUAUUUUUAUUAUUGCUCCUCCUUCCCUAGGAAAAAAAUUUAAUUUAAUUUACAUUCUUCCUAAUGAGAAAAAUUAAAUAUUAAACUGAUAAGAACAGCUACUACACUUGAUCUUAGCCAAAAGGCUGAGAAGUGAAGAGAAAUUAAAUAUUAAGGAAUAAAAUUUUGACAGGUAGGGUUGAGCCUUGGAGGACCACAAACUAUGAUAUCUGAUGUUUUUGUUCCUCAACAACCAAUUUUAAUCUUGGGAGUUCAAAAAUGCUGUUAAUGGACACACCAAUUUAGAUGACUAACCCUGGCUAUCAGGGCAGAGAGGAGAGCUGUUGAACAUUCUGAUAGAUCUUAUAACCGUAUGUGUGCAACUAGUGGAACACAUGACACCGACAUUACUCUCAGCUCACAUCAACUAAUGACUUACAAGGAAGCUGUGCUUCAGUGUGGGUGGCUAAUUAUUCAAACUUGCAUUCUGUAUGAUUAAACCACAUGGAAUUUCACAUUUGCUUUUGUUUUCCAUAUAUUUUAUGGGUCAUAUAGAUUAUAUCUCCACCUUUCACCCACUGCCUGCCUUUUUUAUUAAAUGUGAGCUUUGUAUAAGGCUUUUGUCUACUUUUUGUCAUAGCUCUGGGCUGAACUUUUAGAUUCAUUAGUCUCUGAUUUGUGGCAGUUACCUACAUUUUUACUUACAAUUUUAGAUAAAUAAAUGCCGGCGUGUUCACAGGCAGGAAAACACUGCAUUGGUAGAUAAGGGCCAUUCCAUGCUGGGCUUGACUGGUUGCCACCAACUCUGACAUCCCUGACCCCUUGGCAGAGAAAGAAUGUAAAUGAGCGAGAAUAAAGAGCCCCAGGUAGCUUCUGUUUGUUUUUACAAGAGAACCAGAGCUAGGUGAUUUGGGAGAAUGCCAGAUAUUAUAAACACAGAGCCAGAGAAAAAGAACAAGGAUGGCAAGAAGAGUCCAGGGACUGGGGGAGGUGCACUUGCAGGGGGUGGAGGUUGGCCCAGAGGAAGGUUUUCAUUCAUUUCUGUGUGUAGAAUUUUUAAGAUUAACUUGCUAAUUUUUUUAUUGAAGUCAAGCAAGAUUUUAAAUCAUUUAUCAGGGCUCAUAGAGUACCUAUUUAUAGAAGUCAGAAUAAAAGUAAAUGAACCAUGAAUGCUAACACACAUCUAGCAAAUUUAGUAAGAUUUAAAAGUUAAAUAAACCAAUGGAGCCUGCAGAUUUUCUCCAGGGCCCCUUUACAAGUUUUAACUUUGUUUCCAUUCCCCCCCACUUCAUUUUACACACUGUCAUGUGUGAUUCUUUUAGCCUUAGCUUUUAGAAUACGAAAAUGAUUUACAAGCCUGUUUUUAGAGGCUAUUUCAUUUUUAGUUAAACGUUUACAUGAUGCUGGCUUCCUAUGUAACUGCUGAAAAACAAAAGUUUUUUUUUUCUUUUUUACAGGUGCUAGACUGUCAAUCAGGAUAAAGGAGAUUGUAUGAAUUAUUUGUUGUUGCAUAACAAAUUGCCACAAGUAAAACAACAAACAUUUAUUAUCUCAAAUUUUGUAUGGCUUAGGUGGGUCCUGUGCUUCAGGGUCUAUUACAAGGCUGCAAUCGGUUGUUAGCCAGGACAGGGAUCUCAUCUGAAAGCUCAACCGGGAAAGAUCCACUUCCAUGCUCCCAUGGUUGCCGCAUAAUCCAGUUUGUUGAGGGCUUUUGGACUGAGGGCCUCAGUUCCUAACUGCUUUGGAGGCCACCUUCAGUUCCUGGUUAUGUGGGCCUUCUCAACAUUGGAACUUGCCUCCUCAAAGCCAGCAAGAGAUAGUCUGCUGGAAAGACAUCCACCAUCUUUGCUAUAUUCUGUUGGUUAGAGAGUCACUAGAACAGCCGACACUAAAGGGCAGGAGAUUACACAAGCGCAUUAACACCAGAUCGAGGGGCACCUUAGGAUCCUAGGCCAAGGAGAUAUGUGACUCCAUCCCAACAAGCCUUCAGGAUCUUAGAUUCUUUGAGGGAAGAGACCUUUUUUUCGUAGUUAAAAUAUUUACAAAACCUUUGUGAGGUCAUAGCUAGCGCUUUGUGCUGAACUGGAUUGUGGAGCCCUGGGCUAGCACUGUGCAGGGCAUGAAAGACCAACCACUCUGUAAAUGCACAUAAAGAACAACCUCCUUGAGCAAUCUCAAGCAAGAGAAAGAAGAGGCUUCCGAGCUCCAGCAAAACAAUGGGAAAAAACAUACCCUUAUCUUUUCCUUCUCAUUUUCAAAGGUACCGUGAAUAUAAGUAGAAGAAAGACACCGUCUCUUCCUUUAAGGAACUUACAGUCUUAUGGAAGAGACACAGAUGGAAGUGCACAAUUACCGAAUAUCAUCAAAAAGCCUGAGAAAAAGUUAUGCAAAAGCUACUGUGUGAGCACAGAGGCUGUAAACCUAAUCCUAAGUUGCAGGGUGAGCAACAAGGCACUAUUUUGGAAGCAGAGAACAGCCCUCACCAGACACGGAAUCUGCUGGUGCCCUGAUCUUGGAAUUCCCACCGUCUAGAACUAUCGUUUAAAUGAGAGUUUGCAGAAGAUGAAAGGGGAGUCUUGCAUUCAGCAAUUUGCCCUGUAUUUAAUGAGCCAGCCACCUUGUGUCUUCCCCUCCUAUGACAUAGCCCUUCAGCUCACCCUACAAUUGCCACAUGAAAACUUCUCUCAUGAAACCCACAGGGUGCAAGUUCUCUCCUGUUGCCCUGAGUGCCCACUCCCAGGCCCUCUGUAUGAGUGACACUUCAGUCUGCCAUGGAACCUGGCCCUGCUCUGGCCUGGCUCCUGCUCCUGAGCCUGCUGGCGGAUUGUCUGAAAGCUGCUCAGUCCCGAGACUUCACAGUGAAAGACAUUAUCUACCUCCAUCCUUCAACCACACCAUAUCCUGGUGGAUUUAAAUGUUUCACCUGUGAAAAGGCAGCAGACAAUUAUGAGUGCAACCGAUGGGCUCCAGACAUCUACUGCCCUCGAGAGACCAGAUACUGCUACACUCAGCACACAAUGGAAGUCACAGGAAACAGUAUCUCAGUCACCAAACGCUGUGUCCCACUGGAAGAGUGCUUAUCCACUGGCUGCAGAGACUCCGAGCAUGAAGGCCACAAGGUCUGCACUUCUUGUUGUGAAGGAAAUAUCUGUAACUUGCCACUGCCCCGAAAUGAAACUGAUGCCACAUUUGCCACGACGUCACCUAUAAAUCAGACAAAUGGGCACCCACGCUGUAUGUCAGUGAUAGUGUCCUGCUUGUGGUUGUGGUUAGGGCUCAUGUUAUAGUGGCUCAGUGGCUCCAUGUGUUAAUAGCGAUCCAUGGGGAUCUCGAUGGUCCACAGACCUGCAUGAGUCAUUGGCCUGACAGUAAUUACACAUGUGAGACACAACACUCUUGGAGGUCAUCACAGCCAAGCAUUGCCACUUACCAUGAGGAAUAAAUGUUGCUUCAUUGUAGCCAUUUUGAGUCUAACCGAGACUCAUCAAAGCCUUCUGUCAGUACAGCCCAAGUUCCAUACCAUAAACGUUUGUUUUCAUUCCAAGAAGUAGUUCUGCAUUUAUCGAGAUCUGGGGUUCUUAAUUUGGAAGAAUACAUGCAUGAGAUGCAGUAGGUCCUGAGACUGUAAGAUAUUAGGAGUAUGUUAUAGGGGCAUGUAUAGAUGUGGGCUUUUCAGGAGAAAAGUAACCAUUGGUUUAAAUAUAAUCAUGAGUUCAUUUGUAGCUUUAGAAUUUUAAAACAUUGACUCCAAACUGAAUGGACUAUUUCCUUGGAAAUUCUGACUGAGUCCCUGGAAGAGUAGUAAUUCCAACAAUUCCAGCCAUUUGUUCAAUUAAUUUUCCCAACAUUCUUCUCCCAGUGCUGGGAAUCACAUUUCCUCUGUUCUGUGCAGAAGACAAAAAGGCAAUCAUAAAAGUUUGUUAUAUUUGUGGGGGUGCCUGGAGGAGGAUUUUCCUCAACUUAAUGGAGCCACUGUCCAUAAAGUGGCUGUUAUCCCUUCAUAUAAUUGGUGAGAUCAGCCUUCUCCUUGACUUGGCACCUAAUUAUGCUUCAUGAGAUCCUAGAUUCCACCUGAGUCAAUUGUGUCCAGAGCCCCAAACCAGGAUGGAGUUGUUUUCCCCAGAUAUGGGGUUCUAUUCAGCCAUAGAUAAUCUAGACAGAGGAUUUCAGAAUGAAAGGAAAAAUGUGUGGAGAUUAGUCCUAGUUCAUUCUGAGGGCCGACUAAGUGGCUCAGCCAGCUUCUUACUCCAUCUGCAGUUCAUACUGCCAAAGAGCUCCCACUUCCAAAUCCCCAGUGACUUUAUGGAGAAGAUUCUGCAUUAAAUUGUCUUUCGAAUGAUGGGGAAGCAAGGCAUAAUAUGCGAUGAUGAGGAGAAAGUAGACCAGUGAGGUGAUUGCAAGACUAACAAGGAGACUCAAUGGGAAGUUUUUCUUUCUUUUAGAUAUUGCUUUUGAAGUAGAUGGUAAAAUUUUUGUCAUCCUUCUUGUAUUUUUUGUACCCCAAGUUACAAUUUUUCUUCUUCCUUGUAAAUAAUUUAAACAGUAUUUAUUUUUGUAAGGCAUAACUAGAAACUAAAAUAUAUUCUAAAAAAUUCAUUAUUCUGAACAAAGUGAUCAAAUUAGAAUACAUAUUUUUCAACAGUGGUAGAGCUUUUAAUAUAUGUUUAUUGAAAGUUAUCUAUAAUACUUGCACCAGUGUUGAAAAAAGUUAACAUGUAGGCAAGAGCAAUAUGUUUGUCUCAAGGAUUUUUCCAUGGUUUCCUCAGUGAUGGUGUCCUGGAAUUAUUCAGGUGGUGACCAUCACUGGUCUAAGUUUGUGUGCAGGGUUUUCAGAUGUGUUUUUGUGAAACUUGGUAGAACCAUGGCUAAUAAAGAGGACAGUGUUGUCAGGGUCCAUCUGCCCUCCAUAGAAAAAUGUCUCUGGCUCAUAAAAUGAGACUCCCUCAGGGACUAAAUAUGAACUGACAGCAGUAACUCUGAUACAGAAUAAUCUAAAUUGCAUCAAAUGGCCUUAAUUCAGAGUUUGUUAGGCUUAUCAGUAUGUUGCUUUUAAUUGGGGUGGGAAAGUAGAGGGAGAGAAAGCAAGACAUUUAUUAAGCACCUCGUAUGUGCCAGGCACUAUGCUAAGCACUUUACAUAAGUUAGGAUUAAUCCCUGCAAGAAUCCUAUAAAGAAUGUUACUAGCAUUUACACUUCCCAAAUGAAGGUACCAAAGCUCAAACGCAAUGUUGUGAAGCUGUUUCCUUCAGAUUUAGGUUAUGUGGGAUGAUGUGGGAUUGAAGAGGAAAGAAAGGUGGGAUUAUCCCCCUAGGAAGACUUUCAGGCCUGACUUCAUAGGAAUUCAUCCAUCUUAUCAUGUGGAGUUUAUCUCACCCUGCUGUUGCAGGAUGCUAUUUGCAUGUGUCCCCAGGUGAUGUUUUUUCUUUGGGGAGUAGGGGUUUGGCUUCCUCAUUCAUCCCUCUUGCUAAAAGAGGAGAUAGUUGAUGUUGCAUCUAAAGAUGCUAUAAGACAAUGAAAGUUUGAUGUUGUACAUACCUACAAGUACCAUUUUUGUGCAUGAUUACACUCCACUGACAUCUUCCAAGUACUGCAUGUGAUUGAAUAAGAAACAAGAAAGUGACCACACCAAAGCCUCCCUGGCUGGUGUAGAGGGAUCAGGUCCACAGUGGUGCAGAUUCAACCACCACCCAGGGAGUGCUUGCAGACUCUGCAUAGAUGUUGCUGCAUGUGUCCCAUGUGCCUGUCAGAAUGGCAGUGUUUAAUUCUCUUGAAAGAAAGUUAUUUGCUCACUAUCCCCAGCCUCAAGGAGCCAAGGAAGAGUCAUUCACAUGGAAGGUCCGGGACUGGUCAGCCACUCUGACUUUUCUACCACAUUAAAUUCUCCAUUACAUCUCAAUAUUGGUAAUGGCUUAAGUGUAAAGAGCCAUGAUGUGUAUAUUAAGCUAUGUGCCACAUAUUUAUUUUUAGACUCUCCACAGCAUUCAUGUCAAUAUGGGAUUAAUGCCUAAACUUUGUAAAUAUUGUACAGUUUGUAAAUCAAUGAAUAAAGGUUUUGAGUGUAUCUUACCAGGCUCCUCCCUGCAAAUGCACAUGUCAAUCAAUGAUUAAUGCACCCAGGUUAUGUACAAGGCACUGGGCUUAGCACCACAGGGAACUUCCUUCCAGAGGCUUGCUUUCUAGUUGUGUAGACAAGAAUACAUGCAUGAGAAGAUACAAGACAAUUCACCCAUGCCAAAUGAUUCAUACAGGCUGUUUAAGUACUGCAGAAAAUAAAAGAAGGAAAGGCUACCAGACUUUUCAAUAAGGUCUACAGCUUCCCAAGAGCAUGUCUUUGUUAAAUCAGGAAAUAUAAAAAUUAUGUGUGUAUGUGUAUGUAUAUAUAUAUACCACCCUAUUAACUAUUUUAAAAUCGUAUUCUAUUUUGGGGGUUGUGUUAAUGAUGAUGAACCAGAAAAGAUUUUCUCUUGAUGGUUUCUUCAACAGGAAACAGAUAUUGGAAUAGUGUACAUGUCAUUUUUAUCUAUACAAUGAAUUUAUUAUAUUUUUCUUAGUAAAGUGAUAGACAUUGAAAGCAA